UUGUAGCUUAAAAAACCCCUACUACCCAGCAAAAGGAAAGCAGUAUUUGUGGAGAUUUGAUUAUGGCAACAUCUAAUAAGUGAUUCCAUUGUUCACUGGGUUCUUGUACUGCACCAUGAGGUAGGCAUUGCCCACAAAUGAGAAAUAUUUGACUUUAUGGCAAAUUAUCACUAACAAUACAAAAUAUUUGAAAGCUCUUUAACGUUUUCUCAGUGAGGAGCCUCACAAACCUGUACAUUUUUUAUUGGUUUUUAAAAGAGGAAGAAAUAGAUGUCCAGUGAGAUUGACUUGCCCAAGACCUCCCAUCUUGUGUCUGAAGCAGAAUUUGGAACCAGGCCCUCUGACUUCCAAUCCUAUGCUCAGCCGACUACCACUGGGUCCCCACAUUCUAGGGACGUCAGGAGUAAAGCAGGAUGUGGUGGGGCCUGCAGUGUUUUUUUUUUUUUUUUUUUUUUUAAGGAAAGUGAAGAUUAAACAAAACUUCCUUUGGCCACCUAUAGCUCUGAGGGCAGUGUGCAACCCUUCAGCCAGAAGCUUUCUUGUCUGCAGGAAAAGGUCCUGGGUGGAGCCACCUGCAGGAUGUGUAGCCUGGAUAUGGUGAGGCAGUGCACAUGGUGUCCAGCGAGACGGAGAAGGGUGGGAAGAGAGCAUAAGCAUCCCAUUACUGCAGCCCAACAUGUAUGGAAUGAUGGAGCAAUGGGACAAGUACCUGGAAGACUUCUCCACCUCGGGGGCCUGGCUGCCUCACAGGUAUGAAGACAACCACCAUAACUGCUACUCUUACGCACUCACGUUCAUUAACUGCGUUCUGAUGGCAGAAGGUAGACAGCAACUGGACAAGGGUGAAUUUACGGAGAAGUACGUGGUCCCGCGGACAAGGCUGGCAUCCAAGUUCAUCACACUCUACCGGGCGAUACGGGAGCAUGGCUUCUACGUCACUGACUGUCCCCAGCAGCAGGCACAACCCCCUGAGGGCGGCGGUUUGUGCUGAGAGCUAUGUAAGCGCAGCCUGGACGCUGGAGGGUAGGGUGGUUGCUACCUUUAAUCAGUACUAUGGAUUUCUAAAUGCAUUUAACUGUGGUUAAUAAAAGCGUGUAUGGGCCGGGCAUGGUGGCUCACACCUGUAAUCCCAGCACUUUGGGAAGCUAAGACAGGUAGGUCACCUGAGGUUGGGAGUUUGAGACCAGCCUGACCAACAUGGAGAAACCCCGUCCUUACUAAAAAUAUAAAAUUAGCUGGGCAUGGUGGCGCAUGCCUGUAAUCCCAACUACUAGGGAGGCUGAAGCAGGAGAAUCGCUUGAACCCGGGAGGCGGAGGUUGGGAUGAGUUGAGAUCGUGCCAUUGCACUCCAGCCUGGGCAACAAGAGUGAAACUCCAUCUCAAAAAAAUAAAAAAUAAAAAAUAAAAA